AAAACCAGUAGCAUCAGCAGCAGCAGCAGCAGCCGCCGCCGCCACCACCGCCGCCACAGCAGUAGCAUUAGCGGCAGUAGCAGCAUUUAGCAAUAGCUUUAACAGCUAUAGCGACAGUAGCAGCCGCCCUCCUCUCUCCCUCUCGCGGACGGCCGCAGCCACCGCACAGAGCGGGCUCCAGGCGCCGAGCGCGCAGCCCGCUCGCUAGGUAGCUCCAGCCGGGGCGAGCGACAGUGUAAGCGAAGCACGGACCCUUGGAGCAGCCGGGCAGCCGCGGAGGCUCUGAGUUUCAGGGCCAGAGCCCGACAGCUCUGACUCCAUCUAGCGCGGCGGCGGCGGAGCCUGAGGGAGCGAGCGAGGAGAGAGGCGCGUCCACCUGGCGGGCCCAGCGUAUGGAGCUGAGGCAGAGGCGGCGGCGGCGGCGGCAGCAGUAGCAGCGGCGGUGGCGGCUAAGGCAGCUCGAACAGCUGCGGCGACGGCGACAGCCCAGCCUUGACUGCGACCGCGCUAGCUACAGCGCCUGCUGCCUGAGCCCGCCAGCGACGUGCGCCUCGGGAGUCGGCCUGUGAGGUUGGACAGCAUUUGGACUUGGAAUGAAACAAUAAGAGGUUAUAUUCAUGGAUAACCAACAAGAUAAGGCUAUUGUUGCCUCAGCCAACGGAGAAAACACUCUGAUUAAUGGGGUCAAAGAAAAUGACUCAGAGGACCAGGAUGUGGCAAUGAAGUCAUUUGCAGCUCUAGAAGCUGCUGCACCUAUCCAGCCUACACCGGUGGCACAAAAAGAGACCCUGAUGUAUCCCAGAGGUCUCCUGCCUCUACCCUCUAAGAAGCCCUGUAUGCAGAGCCCGCCCUCUCCUUUGGGCCUGAUUGAAGCACCCGAACAUGCUGCUAAUAGUGCUUCUGUGAAUGCCAUCUCCCUCACAUCUGGCAUUGCAAAAGGCCUGAACACAUGGUCACUUCCCAAUGAAUGUGAGAAAGCUCCAUUUGCCAUAAUGGAGCCUGCAGGCAUGUCAGCUCUGAAUGGGGACUGUCUCAUGCAGCCAAGUCGGACUUGCUUAGGCUGCUUCAUGGAAUCCAAGGAUGCAGUAGAUCCUGAGCCAGGGAUCAGUCUGAAAGUUGGUGAUCUAAAUAGGGAUUAUGAAACGUGUGCAGUCUCUGAUAUAGGGAUUCAGUGUAUUAAUGCUGGAGAAAAUAUGAAAUAUGGAGAGCAGCUGCUCUCAGACCAGCUCCUAGGCUUCCCCCUGCAUAAGUCAAGGGCAGGAGACAGACGAGAAACUGAGAAACCUGACAUUGACUUGGAGGAUCCGGCUCAGAAAAGCUAUUAUGAGGCAUUACUGUUAGACAAGUGCAAUACAGAAGAAGCUUUGCUUGCAAAUUCCAAUCAGGAUUGGGGUUACUUCGAGACUUUUAUUAGUGAAAGUAAGAUUGAACUGCUUGACCUCUGUUCCAAAAAUGAGCUGUCUGUCAACCUAUUCUCUGAAGAAGAUGUGGAUAACUACAUGUUUGAUGAUGAUGAAUCAACACUAGGCAGUGAUGUCUGCUCCCUGAAAAUUCGAUAUGAAUCCUUUCAGGACAAUGUUCGAGACAAGACUACUCUUUUGAUGCAGGAAGAUGCCCAAUUCAACUUUUUUCCCAGCGUCUUUACUACCUGCCCCAAGCGAGAGUCUAAGAGUGGGGCCCUGAAGCAGAGCAGUGAUUUUUCCCAAUUCAAGGUCCCUGAUGUGAGCAUCAUCUGGGGGGAGGAAGAUAAAAACUUGGACAAGAAGAAAGGCAAAGAGGAAGGACAGGAAGACAAAGGUGUAGAGAAGAAAGAUGGAAAGGAUAAUGGAGAAAAGCCUGCCUUAAAUAAACCAUGCAGUGGGACUGAAGUAGAGCAACUUAAGAAUCCAAAGCAGGGCCAUCUUGCUAAUUCCCUGGAGACAUCAGGGAGUUUCAGUGAUGAUAGUUCCUUCAUUGAGAUCUCAUAUGAUGCUAUGGGUGAGAUCAAGGACUGUAGUCGCUAUAUGGCUCGGGACACUAAUUCUGGCAGCUCCUCCUCCCAACAGAACUAUGGGCUGCGAGCCAAGAGAAAAGUCAGAUACAGUGAAGAUUAUCUAUAUGAUGUUGACUCACUAGAGGGUGAAAAAGUAAAUGAGAGGAAGGAAUGGCUGCCAGUUGGUUCCAAAGAGGAAGAUGAUGAUGAAUGGUGUCCCAAAAAGAGAAGAAAAGUAACCCGUAAGGAGCCCCCUGUUAUUAUCAAAUAUAUCAUCAUUAAUCGCUUUAAAGGUGAGAAGAACAUGCUGGUGAAGUUGGGUAAGGUGGAUGCCAGUGAGACAACAGUGAAUUUGAGUGAGAAUCAGCUCAACAAAUAUGCCAAGCUGGCACCCUUGAAAGGCUUCUGGCAAAAGAAGAAGAAGCAGAGAAACACCAACACGGACUCCAUCAAGACACCUUUUUCCCAAAAGCAAAGCUUUGAACCAGGUAGCUUUGAGGUGUCAUUUCUGCCACCUGCUCGCAAACGAAAAUCUAAACUUGGCAACAGGCACAGGAUUCAAAGAAUCCCAUCCAUUGAAAUUUCAGCAAGUAGUAAACAGAUUUCAUUAUGUAAUGAUCAGAGGCACGCUAGUAAUCAUAAAGAAGAUGGAGGCCUAAAAGGUACACUGAAGUCAGCACCUCUGGGUGCUCCUAGCUGUGCAAAUGGAUCACAUUUAAAUGACAUCACAGGCCCUGACUCAGUGAAAGUCAAAGCCCAAGACACAGAGUUUAAGGGGCCAGAGAGGAAAGUGCUCAAUAAAAUCAAAUUUAAAAGUGAAGCUAGGUUAAAAUCUAAGAAAGUCAAAGCUGCUGGGCAAGAAAGCAAGCCAAUUGUUCAAAUGAGCCCUCUCUUGGAAAACCAAUCCUCAAAGGCUAAUUUAAAGAAUGAAGUUAUUCCUGGGACAUCAAACAGUUCCCGUCUAUCUGAAUUUCAUGAGGCAAAGGCUGCUAAGAGUUCCACUUUUCUACCAACGACAUGCUCUUCUGAAAUGCCUUUAUCAUCUGCUAAUGUUACCACUAAUAUACCUGUUAUCCCGGGAGGGUAUCUGCAGACAUUGUUAGAUGCUUCUGACUUGUCAAAUAACACUAGUAUCUCAUACUUCAGCCACCAUUCUCCAGAGCAAAAUGAAGGCAGCCUCACUCAAACCGAAAAAUCAUUUGUACCCCUCCAGCCUACCCAGGACUGUGUGCUCACCUCAUCCUCUGACUCUGAGCUGCAGCAGUCAUCUCAUAACUUCAAAAUGGAAUCAAGCAACUAUAGAAAUGUGUGGCCCAACAAGGCUACUUCUGGCACCCAGGAAUUCAUGGCUGAAGUCUCAAGGGAGAUAGCCCCAACCCAAUCCAGUGAAUUUGGAGCCUCCCAAGUAGUCUCCAUGGAAAAUAACCUCACACCUACAACAUACAAUCCAAUCUGUCUCAAUAGUGGUGGCAGUAAUUGCAACAAGGUCCUGUAUGACUCCAUGCAAGAUACCCAACUCCCAUCUGAUGACUCUUACCAAUUAUGUCACUUUAAUAAUGGAGAGAUCUGCUUUCCUUUCCAGCAGGGGCCAGUCAAUAUGGAUGAUGGUCGGCUCUUUAGCUUUGAUUCAAUGGCCCCACUCUCUGUCAGCUCAAGUAAUUAUUGCUCCUUAAGCUUGAAGUCCUGUGAAAAGGAUGGCGAUGAUGAUAUCACUGAUGACUUCCUGGCCCAUUGCAGCCCUAAGCUGGUGAUCCAGCAAAGCAUUGAUGAGAUAGCACCACUAAAGGAGUCCACUGACCUCCUGGAUAUAUCCAACUUCACCCCUGACAAAUUCCGCCACUCUUCCCUUUCAGAGAUGUCCCCACCGGACACCCCUAGUCUUUCCCCUCAAAUUACCAGAUGUGAGAGUAUGAAGACACUAGGAACACUAAAGGGGUUCCAAGAGGGUGUCCCAGGACCAUUGGACAGUGUGGAAAAAAUCAAGUGGGACUGCAGUACCCUUUCACGGCAGGUCCAAAUGGAGGAUGGAUUUACUUUAAAUAAUCACCAGUUUCAGUUCCAUAUGUUCAAUGAUGAGGAUUCUGUCAGCCUGCUCCAAAAAAACCCUUGCCUGUCAACAUUUAAUGAUCCAUCUGGUCAAAUUAGUACCAACAACAAAGUGUCAAAAUCAAGAAAGAAAAGUUCACCCAGCAAGAGUGGGGCUAUGAACCAAAGCUCUUCUCAGAAAAACACCAGGAAAAAAUCCCUCAAAGGUAACAACAAGGGGAUUGAAAAACCACCUGGCAAAAACUCCCGCCAGGUCCCUAAGUCCACAAAGAAAGGGAAAUACAUGGCUGCCAUCAAUGGAGAGAAAAUGCAAAUUGGCAUUGGCCGUGGGGGAAGCCAAACCAACACCAUAUCCUCCACUGGGAAGACAUUGGCUGAAUGUAUCCAACAUGGUGGCCCUAUGGCCUCUAUGAAGAUGCCAAGUCAAAAGGGACUUUCUGGAGAUUGGGCCUUGGGGAAGGAGAGCAGCCCAGGCUGGAGUGAUAUGAGCAUGGGCACCAACACCAACAGCCUUCUGGAUGAUGACCAACGGGAAUUUCAGGAGCCUUCCUAUAUCUUGUCCAACAUUGCCUCUGGUAUGGCAGAUGUGCAGAGAUUCAUGAUGGCCUCCAUAGAGCCCCUUUGGGAACCCAUGGAGCACCAUGGGGAUCCCAACAUAUUCUACUCCCCUGAGUCCAAUAGUCUAAAAUUAAAAACCCUCAAAAUAUUGGCUGGGACACCACAGGAGUCUAAGAAAAAGAUCAACAGUGGGUCCCAAGGAGCCACUAAGAAUCACAGGUCAAUCAAGGGUGUGAGCAAAAGCAAUGGGAAAACAGCAAUAGGUGAUCCUGGUCGUGCAAACAUGCCUGGUUAUAACGAGGACUCUCGCUCUACCUUCUUUGAUAAAAAGUAUAGUAACAUGAGCACUUUAGGCAAUAACGGACCGACACACAAAAAGUUGUAUCGUCACAAAUCCAGCUCCAAGGCCCUGAGAGAUGAGAAAUGUAAGGGAAAGCACAUGGAGCGAGAACAGGUCCACAAGGAUGAGUCUGGGACAGCUUCUUUUGAAAAACUGAGGGAUUCCGACUACAAUCUCCUAAAAGCAGAAACAACCUUUUGGGUUUUACCUGUGUUUGAAGAAGAGACUCGCAUUUUCCAGAAAGACAUUUGAUGUUUGUGUUUUAUUUCUUUCAAAAUAUGCCUUGUGGUAUGUAUGUUGACAUGUAAGUGCUUAAAGAAAAGAAUUUUAAAUUGUGGGAAUACGUCUUUGGAGCAAACUUUAAUCUCAUGUUCUAUGUAAAAGACUUAAAAAGUCAUACAGUUGCACAAGUAGUUUAUGCACUAUUUACCCACAAGGAAAAAAUUGAAAACAUUGUGCCAAACUACAAACAAGUGACUGUACUGUAUAUAUUUUUACUUCUAUAUCAACAUUUGGUUGUAUUUGGGGAAGUUGUCCCUGUUAAUUUACUAGAAACAUUCCAGUGAUUCUUGCUAUUAACCACCCCCACUUAUGUGGAUAGCACCUGUAGAUCAUGGUGGAAAAAUAUGUUGUGUUACACAAUUUACCAAAAUUAAAGGAUACUGUUUGAAAUGUGCCAAAUUUUCUUACCUCAUCUCACAGAUUCACCCACAGUUUAAAGCUCAUUAAUUAUUUUUAAAUGGAUAUAUACACACCCAAACAUAUAUAUGUAUAUGUUUGUGUGUGUGUGUGUGUGUGUAUAUAUAUGUAUAUAUAUAUAUACACACACACACGUUCUUUUAAAGUUUUAGACUCUACUGUCCUGUGUGGAAACAUGAACAGCUAAACAAGGCAAAAUAAAGAUUUUCUUGUUCCAUUGUGUAAGGGUUAAAAUUUUGGAAAAGUCUGAAGGCCACAACAGCUAAGUCCAUCAGGGACCCAAGUAUAUGCAUUUACAGAACGUUUUACAAGGAAACAAAACAGCUGCUUUCAAAGUUUGUUUUCUAAAAGCAAAAUCUGUAGCUGAAAAUUAUUUAAAGUGCAAAGUUAUAUUGCUGAUACUUUAUAUCUCAGUUUUAUAUAUUUUAUAAUAGUCUGGGAUAAAUUAUAAAAAUAGCUAUAAAAUCAACACUAAUGAUAAAUGAAGUAUAUAGAAUGCUUUUAUUUAAAUAGUUUCCUAAAUGUUUUAUUCCAGUUUUGUCAAAAGUGCACUCAUAUCAUGGCUUUAGUGUUCUUUCAGUGUUUAAUCUUGCAAUGCCAAUGUCAUUUAAAGAAAAUGUUAAGGCAUCCCAGUUCAACCAAAUUUUUCUUCUUAUGAGUAAAGUACAUUUACUAUCAGAUAAGAUGAACAAUUUGUGGCAACAACUGAUUUGGGCCAUAUACCCUUAGUCUGAGGAUAACCAAUAUUUGAUGCCACACACUAAACUUAAAUCUCAAUUUUAAGUACAAAUUUUUAAAUCACAUUUUUUAUUCAGUACUCCCCCUACUUUUUAAAAAAAAUUUCACAGCCCCAACAUUCCUCACUACUACUUUUUCUUCCCUUUUAUUCACCACUUGACUUCUAACAUUUGAUCUCUUUUCUUUGCACAAUUGAAGGCCUGUGCAUCUGAUGACUGAUGCAUUAUGGCACAGAUGAGAUAAUGGAUGUGAGAGCGCUUUGUAGAUCAUAAAGUGCUAUACAGAUAUAGGGGAUUAAUAUUAUUAAUAUUGUUAGUUGUUGUCGUUGUUACUAUUCUUAUUAAUAUUGUUACUAACCUAUUAACUUGUGAAUAUAUAGGCUGGGGUGGGAGGGUGGAGAAUAAGUGGGAAGGGAAAAAGGGGAUUUAACAAAAAAAGGGAAGAUGUUUCAAAAGGAAAAUUUUAAGCAAAAUAUGAACCUACCUAGUCAAUGCCACCUAAAUGUAUUCACAAACAGAGAAGCAACAUUUGAAAGUAGUCAGAGAGAAAUGGAAGGAAGCCUGUCAUGUAUAUAAGUAUAUACACUUCCCGGUCCAUGAUUCCUUUCACCAGCCUGCUCUAUUCCUUACAGCUGGGUCGUAAAAUGAACAAGCCUGUGUUCUUGAUCAUGUGUGUUCCCAGCGUCAGUCUCUUGUGUCUGUGGGGAUGAGUGGGUGAGGAGCAUUCUGUGAGGCUGGUACAGGCCCAUUCCUAGGCUUUAAUGCUCUGUUUGCAGUGAGCCCUGGAAAAUUACUUAGUGGAAAGGCACCAGAUGAAACAUGUCUCCUGCCCCAUAGCUACCAUUCAAAAGGGAAAAUAACCAAACUGGAAAACCUUCUUCUAUUUCUCUAUUCUGAUAGCUAGCUGUACUAAAUGCUAUGGCCAGUCCCUAGAAACUGGUCUUUGUUUUGUUUUUGUUUUUGUUUUUGAUUUUUCUGUUUUGCAGCUGAAUUUUGGCUUGGAAUCACCAACUCUGCCUGUAUUGUGAUCCCCAAGACUCCAGACCUCAGAGUCACCUGCUGGCUUAGAGGAGUGGAGUGCUUUCUAUGUAAUGAAAAGGUGGCAAUUAAUGAAAAAAUAAAGAAAAUGUUCCAUUAAUACAAUGUGUUUUUAUAAAAGUAAAUAUGGGAGCAGUUGUCCCAGUUUUUUUUCGGUAUCAGUUCAGCUUUGGAGAAUGGGGUGUGAGUGGGGUAGGACAGCCUGAAACUGUUGGAAACAAUUUCCUUGUGAGAACUUGCUAUCAUAAGUCCUUUGGAAUGGAUAUUCUUUCAGUUGCUCCUAUGGAGCCCAUUAAGGGCCAAUUCUAGGGCAUAGUUCAUCCCUUUCUCCAAAGAGAAUUGUUAUUUUAAAGUACCUUUUUAAUUGGCCUGCAGUGUAUUAUAUGUUUUUAAUAUAUAAAUUAGUGACGCAUAACCAGUCACUUUGUACUGAAACAUAAAAAGAAACAGAGUUUGAGAAAUGAGCAAUAGGCCGAGGCAGAAGAUGUUUAUUCUCUUAAUUGCAUUUAAUAUUCCUCUCAGUACAUUGUGUUCUGAGAUGUUCAUCAUUUAGCAUUUUGUUGGUCCUGUCUCUGCUCUCACAGUUCUUUUUCUUCCUGUCAUAACCAGCUGCCUUAGUAGAGUAUAAAAAUAGUGUUUUGCCCUAUCACUGGUAUCUCAAGUCAGAAAUAUAUAUUAUCCUUGGUCUGAAAUUCCUGAUUACCGCUCCCUUCUAACCUUCCCCCUCUGAGAAGCUGUUUCCUAUUAAUGCCUCCCUAACAGAGUCCCAUUUAAUCUUUACUUUCCUGGAAAUGGUAACCUCCCUUAUUCUUCUUACUUAAUCUCAGACCUUGGUCUUAGAAUUUUUCUUUUAUGGUCUCAUAUCCCACCUGCCCAAAUUGUCAGGGCUCAACAAUCUUAGGCUGCUUUCUUCUGGAAGUUCAGAAGGAAACCUUCCCAUUCUUAAUUGCCUUUAAUUGCUUUGGCUAUUUUCAAAUCUAAUUUUUUAAUUAAAUUUUUUUUAAUUUUUAUAGAGUAGGGGUACAAGGACAGUUGUGUUACAUGGAUAUAUUGCUUAGUGUUGAAAUCUGGGCUUUUAGUGUACCCAUCACCGAAAUAGUGUACAUUGUACCCAAUAGGUGGUAUUUCAUCCCUCAAAUAUAAUUUUAAACACACACUCGUGCCCACAUGGACAAAUUAUAUCACAUGACUGAGGAAACUUAGAAAUUCCUUUUCCCUGAAGAUCUGUUAAGAAUAGGUCUCAUCUCCUGCCCUGGUUAGGUGCUAUAUUAUAUGGAGAAGGGUAUUGAGACUUUGGGGGUCAUGUUUGGGCUGUGAUAACUGGCUUGAACCAGUGACCAUCCUUUCUGCCUCGCCAAGGUCUCUUAUACCAGCUUCUUCACAUAUGCUGCUUCCUCCCAGCUUUCCCUUCUGACUUCUUGUUACUCUGCAACUAUGUGUCAAGGCCUUACCUUUUCCUGAUGUUUUCAAACCUCCUGCAUUACUUUGAUCAUCACUUCUUCAGCCAUCUCACUGAAGUCCUUGGUGCUAGCUGGGCUUUUGUGACAACUUUCACCUUCUCUGAACUUUUUCCUUGCUGGGAAGCAUCUGCGUGUGUGAGGGGGCUACGGAGGGAAGUGUGUGUGUGUGUAAGAGAGAGGCAAAAGGAUGCUUCAAAAGCUAUAAACAACUCUAGCAAGCAUCCUAAGUCCUAUGUGAGGUUUUGCAGUUCUAGUGAAUUUCUGUUUUAGUAGGUUUCAAUUAGCAUUUACUGCCUAAAGGAGAAAAACCAUAUCCAAGGACCUUUUAGCCAUGCUUGCUAUUACCAAGCUGGACCAGUGUGAUGUAGAUCCAACAUGUCUUCAGCUUACAGAUGCUCUCAGAACAGUUCCAAGAAUUGAAGAGAGCUAAGUUUUUAUGCUGAAGAGGAGAAUGGAGCACUAGCUAGUCCUAACUAUUGCUAGAAAUAGAAAUGUUUAUUUUCUCCUUUAUUAUUGAGAAAUUAUCUAAUUUAAGGAGUAACCAUUUUCAUUUAGGGAUUUUUUUAAUGACUGCCCAUCACUACAGAAAUAUGUUCUUUUUAUAAAAUAAAACUAAUGUGAGGUUGGUUUGUUUUCUAAUCAUAAAAUUCACUAAGCCUAUAGUUACAUUUAGAAGAUUUAGUACCAAAAUCAAACUUUUAGUAACAAACAGGAAUCUUGUCAACACAAUGUAGGCCAGGGAUUUUGUAAAGGUUUCUCAAAGACCCAAAUAAGGGAGAAAAAAAUUUUAGUUGGGCUGUUUAACUUGGGAAACACUGUCAUCAGCUUGAGGGUCCUCAGCCAGCAUGUGAUUAUUUUGAUGACAGGACUCAGGCUACCCUUUAAGGCACAUUUUUUACUCAGCAUUAAACACUAGCUACAGUCGUGAAGCAGAGCUCCCAUUGCAGCUACAUACUUGAGAUGUACUCUUGGUUUCAGAAUCGUAACUAAGAGGUAAGGCAUUGGAGAAGGACAAUGUAAAAGACAGAGGUUUAGAACAAAGUUUAUGGUGUGAAUGAGGCUUUCAAAAUCAGUAUCUGGGUAAAUUGAUACUAAAGACACUGAAGAAACACUCAUCCACAUAAGAUGGAAAGGAUGUCUGUCCAUCUAACAAGCUCAGGGGUUUCUGAGUCUCAGAAUGACAUCCCAUUUCAAAAAGAAGAAAAGAGAUAUUGAAAUCAUUCUGCCUGUUUGAGAGAUGACUGGUUAUUUACAGCACAAAAAAAGGCUUAGAAUGAAAACUAGAAGAGGCCUUUUGUUUUUCACUCCCAGUGAGGAGAGUAGAAAUCUUAAGAUGCUCUACUGGGCUACCUGUAGCACUGACUGGAGUUUGCUGCCUACAGAGUUUUGAAUGUACUAGUCCUUAGUUUCCAUAGAACUGAAUGCACCUCUUUAGUAAGUUGCUGAUUUAUGGUGCUAAAGAAAAUGAUUAUUCCCAUUUUUUUCUUCUUCCCCAAGCCCCUUAAGCAUUUAAGAAAAUUUAAAAUAAAAGCGUUAGAGGCCCUUUUUAUGAAUGUAACCUAAGUUUCUGUUUGACAUAUGACACUGCAACUUAAAAAUGUUAGGAAAUUAUUUGCCUUUUUUUUUCUUUUAGAGUUAAGCUUUAUAAAUAAUCUGUAGAAUCAAUUGAAGUUUAAAGCUUAAGGAUCACUCUUAAGACGUCUACAAAAUCUUGUAUAUUUUUAAGUGUGCCAAUUUGUAACAUAUUUUGUAAGUGUAUAUUUUUCUUAGAAAAGUGCUGUGAAGUGUCUGUAUGUGAGAGUUUUCCUUUUUCUGCACCACUAGGUGCUAAUAAAAGGAUAUUUACUUCAAAGUUUCUGGUUUUAGAAACCACAAUACAAAGAAAAAAAAUACACUUUUGUUGGAAAUUUUGUAACACAAAACAUGUUGUGAAAGAGUGUAGUGAUCUUGUGCAAAAAAAAUGAACAUUUGUGAGCUUCUUGCUGUUUUAUAGAUUUUCUUGUAAAUUAUUCUUGUAACACUUCUGGUUUUGUUGUUCUUGUUGCGAAGGUUUCAAAUAUUUGUGACUGAAUGUACGGUGAAACUGUCAUAAUGUUACCUAGCUGAGUUUUGUUAUUGUUUAUGAAAUAAAUAAAAAGAAAAGUUUAAAAUACUGCUUUAGAAUCAUAUGUAUUAGAAAUCAAACCAUUUCUAAUUAAAUCUAUGUCCCAAAUAAAACGUUCUUUAUCAUCUAGAGCAGUGUUUCUCAAACUAUCUGUGGUGAGGGACCAAUAGUUUUUGCAAUCCAUCACAGACCAAUACUAUUAUAAAACACAACAAAAAUGAAUUUCUAAGAAAGUUAAAUGGAAAAAAGAUAUGCAAAAUAAAAGCCCAAAUGUAUUAGAUUUAACAUGUAAAAUUACAUUUCGAGAUAAACAUAACAUAAGGGGAAAGAAACGAAUUGCAAAAAGUUGGUACCCUGUUUGAGACAAGUCCACUCAUCAAUGUCAAAUUGCCAUAGAAGGUUCUAAUCAUACUUUGAAUAAUACUUUGACUAGACCAGCAGCAUUGCCAUCAUCUGGGAACUUGUUAGGAAUGCGAAAUUCCAAGCCCUACACCAAUUCUGCUGAAUGAGAAUCUGAAUUUUAACAAGAUCCCUAGGUGUUUUGUGUGCAUGUUAAAGUUUGAGAAGCACUGGGCUAGAGUUUUGUGUAGGGGAUUCUUUUGCCCCUCAAAUUGAGGAAUCAUCUUCUAGUGUGUCCAGUCUUCAAAGACCUUAAAACAAAUUGUGUCUUUGUUUUGUGAUCCAGAUGGAAUCUGCAGAGAUGCAGUCCUCUCAAAGUGUUAAAGCUGUUUAUUGAAAGUAAUAAAUGCUGAUUUGCCUGGUA